GUAUUCAGCCAGCAGGCUCUGCACAAGGAAGCAAAGUGCAGGGAGCCAGGCUCCACCGACAGCCAGGCACUGGGCAGCACGCACUGGAGACCCAGGACCCUGUGCAGGAGCAGCUCCGGGUGACACGAGGGGACUGAAGAUACUCCCACAGGGGCUCAGCAGGAGCAAUGGGUAACCAAAUGAGUGUUCCCCAAAGAGUUGAAGACCAAGAGAAUGAACCAGAAGCAGAGACUUACCAGGACAACGCGUCUGCUCUGAACGGGGUUCCAGUGGUGGUGUCGACCCACACAGUUCAGCACUUAGAGGAAGUCGACUUGGGAAUAAGUGUCAAGACGGAUAAUGUGGCCACUUCUUCCCCCGAGACAACGGAGAUAAGUGCUGUUGCGGAUGCCAACGGAAAGAAUCUUGGGAAAGAGGCCAAACCCGAGGCACCAGCUGCUAAAUCUCGUUUUUUCUUGAUGCUCUCUCGGCCUGUACCAGGACGUACCGGAGACCAAGCCGCAGAUUCAUCCCUUGGAUCAGUGAAGCUUGAUGUCAGCUCCAAUAAAGCUCCAGCGAACAAAGACCCAAGUGAGAGCUGGACACUUCCGGUGGCAGCUGGACCGGGGCAGGACACAGAUAAAACCCCAGGGCACGCCCCGGCCCAAGACAAGGUCCUCUCUGCCGCCAGGGAUCCCACGCUUCUCCCACCUGAGACAGGGGGAGCAGGAGGAGAAGCUCCCUCCAAGCCCAAGGACUCCAGCUUUUUUGACAAAUUCUUCAAGCUGGACAAGGGACAGGAAAAGGUGCCAGGUGACAGCCAACAGGAAGCCAAGAGGGCAGAGCAUCAAGACAAGGUGGAUGAGGUUCCUGGCUUAUCAGGGCAGUCCGAUGAUGUCCCUGCAGGGAAGGACAUAGUUGACGGCAAGGAAAAAGAAGGACAAGAACUUGGAACUGCGGAUUGCUCUGUCCCUGGGGACCCAGAAGGACUGGAGACUGCAAAGGACGAUUCCCAGGCAGCAGCUAUAGCAGAGAAUAAUAAUUCCAUCAUGAGUUUCUUUAAAACUCUGGUUUCACCUAACAAAGCUGAAACAAAAAAGGACCCAGAAGACACGGCAUCGAAAGCAGAAAGUGUCUGUGAUGGACAAGCUGGUCAGAAGACAUCCGAGAUCCAGGCUAGAGGCACCAAGAAAAAGCACCUGGAUAGCCCCAGGCUAGGACUCGCCUUUAGAAAAUUCUUUAGGCAUAAGGGUGCUGAAAAGUCACCCACCACUUCAGCUGACCUUAAGUCAGACAAAGCCAACUUUACAUCCCAGGAGACCCAAGGGGCUGGCAAGAAUUCCAAAGGAUGCAACCCAUCGGGGCACACACAGUCCGUGACAACCCCUGAACCUGCGAAGGAAGGCACCAAGGAGAAAUCAGGACCCACCUCUCUGCCUCUGGGCAAACUGUUUUGGAAAAAGUCAGUUAAAGAGGACUCAGUCCCCACAGGUGCGGAGGAGAAUGUGGUGUGUGAGUCACCAGUAGAGAUUAUAAAGUCCAAGGAAGUAGAAUCAGCCUUACAAACAGUGGACCUCAACGAAGGAGAUGCUGCACCUGAACCCACAGAAGCGAAACUCAAAAGAGAAGAAAGCAAACCAAGAACCUCUCUGAUGGCGUUUCUCAGACAAAUGUCAGUGAAAGGGGAUGGAGGGAUCACCCACUCAGAAGAAAUAAAUGGGAAAGACUCCAGCUGCCAAACAUCAGACUCCACAGAAAAGACUAUCACACCGCCAGAGCCUGAACCAACAGGAGCACCACAGAAGGGUAAAGAGGGCUCCUCGAAGGACAAGAAGUCAGCAGCCGAGAUGAACAAGCAGAAGAGCAACAAGCAGGAAGCCAAAGAACCAGCCCAGUGCACAGAGCAGGCCACGGUGGACACGAACUCACUGCAGAAUGGGGACAAGCUCCAAAAGAGACCUGAGAAGCGGCAGCAGUCCCUUGGGGGCUUCUUUAAAGGCCUGGGACCAAAGCGGAUGUUGGAUGCUCAAGUGCAAACAGACCCAGUAUCCAUCGGACCAGUUGGCAAAUCCAAGUAAACAAAUCAGCACGGUUCCCACCAGGUUCUCCUGCCACCAAGAUGUGUUCUCCUUACUCCAUCUCCUCCCCAAACACGCUCCAUGUAUAUAUUCUUCUGAUGGCCAGCAAAUGAAAUUCUGCCUAGAAAUUAAGCCCGAGCUGUUGUAUAUUGAGGUGUAUUAUUUACGUCUCUGGUCCAGUCUUUUCUGGCAAAUAACAGUAAAGAUGGUUUAGCAGGUCACCUAGUUGGGUCAGAAGAGUCGAUGAUCACCAAGCAGGAAAGGGAGGGAAUAGAGGAAUGUGUUCGGGUUAAGUGAUGAAAAUGGCAGUGGUGGCCGGGCGUGGUGGCUCUCGCCUGUAAUCUCAGCACUUUGGGAGGCCGAGGCAGGUGGAUCACCUGAGGUCAGGAGUUCAAGACUAGCCUGGCCAACAUCAUGAAACCCCGUCUCUACUAAAAAUACAAAAAUUAGCCAGGCAUGGUGGCACACACCUGUAGUCCCAGCUACUCGGGAGCCCAACGCACGAGAACCGCUUGUACCCAGGAGGUGGAGGUUGCAGUGAGCCGAAGUUGCACCAUUGCACUCCACCCUGGGCGACAGAGCAAGAUUCUAUCAAAAAAAAAAAAAGGCAGUGGCAAGUAAGUUAUAGAAGAGAAAUGCUGCUAGAAGGAAUUAAGCGUUGUAGUAAAUGCGUGCUUAUCCUCUAAGCUUGAAGAAGGGAGACGAAAAUCCAUUUGUUUAAAUUCACAUCUCAAGGAGGGAGAACCCGGGCUGUGUUGGGUGGUUGCCAAUUUCCUAGAACGGAAUGUGUGGGGUAUAGAAAAAGGAAUGAAUAAGCGUUGUUUUUCAAAUAGGGUCCUUGUAAGUUAUUGAUGAGAGGGAAAAGAUUGACUGGGGAGGGCUUAAAAUGAUUUGGGAAAACAAUUGCUUUUGAGGCUCAGUGACAACGGCAAAGAUUACAACUUAAAAAAAAAAAAUAAAUAAAAAAUAAAGGAAGUUGCACGGUUAUUUUGCAACACAAGGGGGCGGCAAGGUCCCCAUUUUUAUCCUGUAAUACUGUAUCCCUAACAAAGAUUUGGUCUCUGCUAUCUUACAUUAUUAAUGUUUCUCAGAUGGCUGAGGGGCUCGCUUCAUCUGUUCCGUCUGACACUUAUCUCAAGUGUGUCUGUCAUUCCUAAUGUUCUCAGGAUGUGCUCUGAUAAAACCCUCCCCAUAACCUCAGUUAAUAAAAAUUUACAGAAGACUUCUCAAAUACCUGAGUUGUUUUUAAUACCUGUACAAAGGAGUAAAUAGGACCCUGAGUCUAUUAAAAUGUAAUUCAAAGUAGCAUAUGAUUGACUGACAGUCAUGUAAACUGUAUCUUUCUUUUUCUGAUUUAAUAAAAAAUACAUUUACUUCUAAA